GGAGGCGGGACCUGCGGCCAGCCCUGGGCGGCCAUGUGGACAGAGCUGGGAGGGCCGGAACCAGAACCCAAGCGUGAUCCUGAACCGGAGCCCGAGCCUGCUGCAGGUAACUAACGCUGGUCUCCCCUCGGCUCCCUCGGGAAGCCGCAGCUCCUGGCUCCGCGUGGGGGCUUUCCUCUCUGGGCCGCGGCGUCCGCAUCUGGGGGCUGGCCUUUCCGCCGUUGCACUGUAGGACUCUCUCCACGUCCCCUAAUCCCAUCCCCCGCCUCUGGGUGACGCUACAGGAGCCCCGAGGACACAGACGCCCCCAGACCUUACCACGUUAGCUCGACCUCAACACUCCUGCCCACUCGGCCCACUUCAACAGAGGGCCCCUGACCAUAGCCCAGAGGCUUGGACAAGCCCAAAGGUUGCGCCCUUUCCCCCGCAGAAGGGGUGAGGUGGGCGCCGCUGCAGUUCCCGCGGAUAGAGAAGGUCCGGUCCUUCCCGCUGUGGGUGAACUGUAAAAAAUUGCCUGUAUUCAGGAGGAUAUGCAAAGCUAGGUUUGUGGAAGUCUGGGGUGAGGCUCCUAUACUUUCUUGCUGUGUGUCCUCGGUGAGUCCCUGAACCUCUCUGAUGCCCAGCCUUCUUCCAGAAUGGGGGUCAUCAUCAACCCUGACCACCCAGGGACUGCAGAGAGGCUUGGCAAAUUUCCCGUGAGAAGACAGCCUGCAAACUGUAAAGCAUGAUGCUCUGUGAGCUGUGAUCUUCCUAUCAGCAAGUGGAGGCCCCAGCAAGAACCCCAUAUAGGCCCCAAGAGUAGGAACGGCCUUGGUGUGGCUGCAAAGGUUUGCCAGCCUUGGCCUAUGACCACCUCUCCUGACUGCUUCACCCCUCCAAUCCUUACCCCAUGGGUUGGUGACUCCCCUUUCCCCUACCUCCUUUUGGUCUCCUCACCCUCAGAGCCAGGCCUGUUGGUGGCAAGGGGGCUGUGUCCCAGCAUAUGGCAAAGUCCUGAGCUAAAUGGAACCCUGGGCACCCCUGGCAGAUCUGCUGACUCAGCUUCCCCCUGUGGGAUAUGAUGAGGUUUCUCUUCAAAUAAUCUGAUCAAUCUUUUAUUCUUUAAUUCUUAGUAUCCCCCCCUUUUUUUUUUUCAUUUUUCUCCUUUUUGCCUUUGUUAGAUGCCCAGGCAUGCCACAGUACCAAGCGUUAUCAGUACCAGCUCACAUUCCUUUGCUUAUUUGGAAAGAAGACUAACUUUCUAGCUCAUUACAGACACCCUUUCCCCUUUCUCUCCACUUUCUUUUACGUGCCCACUCUAUCUAAAAUAAAUCAAAUGUUUAGCCAACCGGGAUUAGUUUAGAUUGUACGACCUGACCCCAGCCAAUGGGGAAAGGGUACAGGGGCAGGACUUGCAUCAGGAAUAAAGGCUCUCGUGCCCCUUUGUUCAGGUGUGCUCUCAUGGCAACUGGCCAAGGAGGCAUCCCUCUGCGCAGAAGUAAAAUUGCUUUGCUAAGAAUCCUGUGUUCGAGUGUUCAAUUUCCUUAGGAUUUUGAGCAUUAUUCCUAACACCCGCAAGGGGAAGGGAAACUUUCUUGGUCAGCAUUGAUUAUUAUUAUUUUUUUUAGAUACAGUCUUGUUCUGUUACCCAGGCUGGAGUGCAGUGGCACAAUCAUGGCUCACUGCAGCCUCAACCUCCUGGGCUCAGGUGAUUGCCCCCACCUCAGCCUCCCAAGCAGCUAGAACUACAGGCAUGCACCACUAUGCUCGGCAAAUUUAUUUUUGUUUUUUUGUAGAGACACGGUUCUUGCUAUGUGCUCAGGCUGGUCUCAAACUCCUGGCCUCAAGCAGUCCUUCCACUUCGGCCUACCAAAGCGUUACCAGCAGUGUCAGCAUGCUGCGCUUCCUGGCACCCCGGCUGCUUAGCCUCCAGGGCAGGACCGCCCGCUACUCCUCGGCAGCAGCCCUCCCAAGCCCCAUUCUGAACCCAGACAUCCCCUACAACCAGCUGUUCAUCAACAAUGAAUGGCAAGAUGCAGUCAGCAAGAAGACCUUCCCGACGGUCAACCCUACCACCGGGGAGGUCAUUGGGCACGUGGCUGAAGGUGACCGGGCUGAUGUGGAUCGGGCCGUGAAAGCAGCCCGGGAAGCCUUCCGCCUGGGGUCCCCAUGGCGCCGGAUGGAUGCCUCUGAGCGGGGCCGGCUGCUGAACCGCCUGGCAGACCUAGUGGAGCGGGAUCGAGUCUACUUGGCCUCACUCGAGACCUUGGACAAUGGGAAGCCUUUCCAAGAGUCUUACGCCUUGGACUUGGAUGAGGUCAUCAAGGUGUAUCGGUACUUUGCUGGCUGGGCUGACAAGUGGCAUGGCAAGACCAUCCCCAUGGAUGGCCAGCAUUUCUGCUUCACCCGGCAUGAGCCCGUUGGUGUCUGUGGCCAGAUCAUCCCGUGGAACUUCCCCUUGGUCAUGCAGGGUUGGAAACUUGCCCCGGCACUCGCCACAGGCAACACUGUGGUUAUGAAGGUGGCAGAGCAGACCCCCCUCUCUGCCCUGUAUUUGGCCUCCCUCAUCAAGGAGGCAGGCUUUCCCCCUGGGGUGGUGAACAUCAUCACGGGGUAUGGCCCAACAGCAGGUGCGGCCAUCGCCCAGCACGUGGAUGUUGACAAAGUUGCCUUCACCGGUUCCACCGAGGUGGGCCACCUGAUCCAGAAAGCAGCUGGCGAUUCCAACCUCAAGAGAGUCACCCUGGAGCUGGGUGGUAAGAGCCCCAGCAUCGUGCUGGCCGAUGCUGACAUGGAGCAUGCCGUGGAGCAGUGCCACGAAGCCCUGUUCUUCAACAUGGGCCAGUGCUGCUGUGCUGGCUCCCGGACCUUCGUGGAAGAAUCCAUCUACAAUGAGUUUCUCGAGAGAACCGUGGAGAAAGCAAAGCAGAGGAAAGUGGGGAACCCCUUUGAGCUGGACACCCAGCAGGGGCCUCAGGUGGACAAGGAGCAGUUUGAACGAGUCCUAGGCUACAUCCAGCUUGGCCAGAAGGAGGGCGCAAAACUCCUCUGUGGCGGAGAGCGUUUCGGGGAGCGUGGUUUCUUCAUCAAGCCUACUGUCUUUGGUGGCGUGCAGGAUGACAUGAGAAUUGCCAAAGAGGAGAUCUUUGGGCCUGUGCAGCCCCUGUUCAAGUUCAAGAAGAUUGAGGAGGUGGUUGAGAGGGCCAACAACACCAGGUAUGGCCUGGCUGCGGCUGUGUUCACCCGGGAUCUGGACAAGGCCAUGUACUUCACCCAGGCACUCCAGGCCGGGACCGUGUGGGUAAACACCUACAACAUCGUCACCUGCCACACGCCAUUUGGAGGGUUUAAGGAAUCUGGAAACGGGAGGGAGCUGGGUGAGGAUGGGCUUAAGGCCUACACAGAGGUAAAGACGGUCACCAUCAAGGUUCCUCAGAAGAACUCGUAAGAGCAGCUGUCAGGGAGGCCCAGUCACAGUCCAGCAAUUCCACAACCACCUUGACGAAUGCUUGCCAAGCUGUUUUAAAGCCAAGAACACCCUUUCUUUGUUCCAAAUUAACUCUUAGAAGAAACCCCACAAAUAAAGCAAUUCAAUCAAGGCUGUUCUAUUUAAAUCAGAGAUGGGGACCAGGCUCAGAGUUCUACCUAUCUAACCCCCAACCACAGCCCCCUUGGUGGCCCAUGAGUUGCUUCCAUGAAAUCUUAGGAGUCUCUGGAGGACAGAUUAAAAACCAGUGAUCUGUAAUUUGUAGCUCUUCCUGCUGAUCCAAGGACUUUCCCAUGGGUGCGCUUGAUGGUUUAGUGGAUCGACUCAACUCAGAACACAAGCUUGGAAAGUGUUAGGGGUUUUGAACUAGGUGGAUACUAAAUCUCGGCCCCACUCUUCAUUGGCUUAACCUAAAAACCAGAGGUGCUUUUCCUUGUCUGUGUGCCAGUUGCUGGCUGUUUUAGUUGCUUGCCCUUCAUUUUGCUACUGAUUUUCCUUAAUUUGUGGGAAGGAGUAGGCAAAGAAUAUGCUUACAUGAUUACACCUGUAAAGUAAGCCCAAACAUCCCAAAUGUCCGUCAACUGAUGAGUGGAUUAAUAAAAUGUUUCCAUGGAAUAUUCCUUGGAUUACUCAGCCAUAAAAAGGAAUGAAGUACUGACACAUGCUGUGACAUCAGUGAACCCUGAAAACAUCCUUCUCAGUGAAACAAGCCAGAGAGAUGUACAAGGCUACAGACUGUAUGAUUCCAUUUAUAUGAAAUAUACAUACUAGGCAAAUCCAUGGAGAUGGAACAUAGAUUAGUGGUUGCCAGGGGAUAGAGGAGUAAUUGUUAGUGGGCAUGGGAUUUGUUUUUGGGAGGUUUUGAAAAUGUUCUGGAGUUGAACAAUAGUAAUGGUUGCAUGAUUUGGUAAAAAUACUAAAAACUAUGGAAUUGUUUAAUUAUGGUAUAUGAAUUAAUUUCUUUCUUUUUUUCUUUUUUUUUUUUUUUUUUGACACGGAGUCUCACUCUGUCGCCCAGGCUGGAGUGCAGUGGUGUGAUCUCGUCUCACUGCAACCUCCGCCUCCCAGAUUCAAGCGAUUCUCCUGUCUCAGCCUCCUGAGUAGCUGGGAUUAUAGGUACAUGCCAUCACACCUGGCUAAUUUUUGUAUUUUUAGUAGAGAUGAGGUUUCACCAUUUUGGCCAGGCUGAUCUUGAACUCCUGACCUCAGGUGAUCCACCCGCCUCAGCCUCCCAAAGUGCUGGGAUUACAGGUGGGAGCCACAACACCCGGCCAUGAAUUAACUCCGUUAAAAAAUAAACGUAUACAUUCUGUGAGCAAA